UGGCCCAUGGGAAGAGAUGAGGCCUCAAAAAAUGAAUGCAUCUGGAGACCUAGCCUCCUUCUCCUCUUUGUACCAACCCAACUCCGAAACCUCUGUAGGGGCCGACCUGCUGGAAAAGAAUCUUGCUGAGAUACAGAACCUGCGCCAGCGCCUGGAGGAGUCCAUCAGUCUCAAUGACCGCCUGAGGGAGAGGCUGCAGCAUGUGCUUAGCAAUGGUGACCAAGGAAAAGAUAAUCAGAGAGUCACUAGCUGUCAACUAGAAAGCUUGGUGUCUCUCUUCCUGUCUUUCCCACUUUCACCUGGGUACGGAAUAGGAGAGAAGAAAUGUACUGGACAGUCCACUGUAGCCCCUCAUUCAUAUACUCAGAGUCACUCUUCUGGCUGUGGCGAGGACAUCCUGUGACAUGAUGCCUAGAGAGUCUGGAAGAAUGUUCUCCAGAACUUUUCCAGCCCUAUCCAACAGAAUUCUUGGGUGGGAACUU